GAGUCGGGGCCUGAGCGUCAAGAGCAUGCCCUAGUGAGCGGGCUCCUCUGGGGGAGCCCAGCGCGCUCCGGGCGCCUGCCGGUUUGGGGGUGUCUCCUCCCGGGGCGCUAUGGCGGCGCUGGCCAGUAGCCUGAUCCGGCAGAAGCGGGAGGUCCGCGAGCCCGGGGGCAGCCGGCCGGUGUCGGCGCAGCGGCGCGUGUGUCCCCGCGGCACCAAGUCCCUUUGCCAGAAGCAGCUCCUCAUCCUGCUGUCCAAGGUGCGACUGUGCGGGGGGCGGCCCGCGCGGCCGGACCGCGGCCCGGAGCCUCAGCUCAAAGGCAUCGUCACCAAACUGUUCUGCCGCCAGGGUUUCUACCUCCAGGCGAAUCCCGACGGAAGCAUCCAGGGCACCCCAGAGGAUACCAGCUCCUUCACCCACUUCAACCUGAUCCCUGUGGGCCUCCGUGUGGUCACCAUCCAGAGCGCCAAGCUGGGUCACUACAUGGCCAUGAAUGCUGAGGGACUGCUCUACAGUUCGCCGCAUUUCACAGCUGAGUGUCGCUUUAAGGAGUGUGUCUUUGAGAAUUACUACGUCCUGUACGCCUCUGCUCUCUACCGCCAGCGUCGUUCUGGCCGGGCCUGGUACCUCGGCCUGGACAAGGAGGGCCAGGUCAUGAAGGGAAACCGAGUUAAGAAGACCAAGGCAGCUGCCCACUUUCUGCCCAAGCUCCUGGAGGUGGCCAUGUACCAGGAGCCUUCUCUCCACAGUGUCCCCGAGGCCUCCCCUUCCAGUCCCCCUGCCCCCUGAAAUGUAGUCCCUGGACUGGAGGUUCCCUGCACUCCCAGUGAGCCAGCCACCACCACAACCUGUCUCCCAGUCCUGCUCUCACCCCUGCUGCCACACACAUGCCCUGAGCAGCCAGGUCCCACUAGGUGCUCUACCCUGAGGGAGCCUAGGGGCUGACUGUGACUUCCGAGGCUGCUGAGACCCUUAGAUCUUUGGGCCUAGGAGGGAGUCAGAGAGGGGGAUGUCUGAAGAUGGUCCUGGCUGAUCACUUCUUUCUUUCCACACUCACACAACGCCAUGCCUUUUCCUGAGAUGGCGCUGGGAGUUCCCACAUGGACAGCCAGGGCAUAAACACUUCCCACCCCGGCUCAGCCAGUUCCUGGAGUCCUGUGCCCCUUUUCAUUGCCACUGAGCCAUUUCUAGAUUCACUGGAGCUCAGGAUUCAUGUGUCCUUCUUUCCCUACUCUACCUUCUACCUUGGUCUGGACACAUUCUGGAACACUGGACACCCUCGCCAGGGCCACUUCUGCACUAGGGCUCUGUGCUGGAACCCAGGCAUGCUGCCAGCCUUUUCUCUGGAUCUGUCAGGCCUCUGUCAUUGACUCAGAUGGACCCCUGGUUUCCAAGUAGAAAGAGGCUAGAUUUGGGCCUUGUCUAGCUGUUGGCUUUGGCCUGAACCGGAACCAGUCUCAGAUGACCACGGGUUUAACCUUCUUAUCCCAGAGACACCCAAUUCUAGAGCUUUAUGGAGCCGUACUUCCCCCUGAAUCCUAGCUCUAGGACAUAGAUCAUGACUCUCAGCCCUUUUACCCAGGAUGGAGCUGGGGCCUGUAUAGCCAUAUUAUUGUUCUAAGUAAGUUCUAGCCCCACCCUCCCGCCUUCUUGAGUGAUACCUAUUACGGAUGAGUUCUGGAAAAGACCCAGCUAUGAUUCAUAAAAACACUUCUGGAUGAAUCAAGAACCAUUUCUUGUUUUUCCUAGAUAAUUCUCUAAAAAUAUGAUUCUUCCAUAUAGAAUGCUAAGCUUAUUUUUACAUGCAGUUUCUAGCUCCUUCAACCCAGCUGAGGUCGUGCCAGGGAGACAGAGUCUGGAGAAGGGCAGAGGAAUUUUGGAAGGAUCCCUGGCUCAUAGUAGGGAAGCUGGGAUGGGGGAGGGGUCAAAAUUAUGGCAUGACUGAACCUGCAUCUGUGUUGGGUGGACAUGAAUACUUAGCUACCUCAGCAGGAAUUCCUUCCAGGUCCCCUUUAAAGCUGAGGUCCUUAGAGUAAUAUGUCCUUAAUAAAAAGGACAAAUGGAUACAGCCUUGACCCUCCCAGUGAGGAGACCCCAAUUCAGCAAUAAGUCUCACCCUUCUCCCCUACAGGUCAGGCCAAGAAGGGUGAAGGCCUCUUGCACUCCAGACCUCAUACGCCCCAACAGCUUCUAAUUGGAUAGAACUUGCUUUACCUUACAGCUCACAACCUCAGCUGGGUUUUAGGUACCCAAAAAGGGCCUGUCUAGAUUUUUUCAGAAAAACGUGGAGUGCUAGGGGCAGCCUGGAAAAGAUGGGGAACCUGCUAGUGAACUAGGAGGGAGACUUCCAUAGCCUCAGACUUGGAUAGGGUAGGCUGAGGGGGCCCUAAGGGAGGGACUAAGGCUCCAAGGCAGGUCACUUUUCCUUAGGCUGUUCUACUUCUGGCUUGUUGCAAGAGGAGUAGAUGCCCCCUCACCCACACAAACCCCACUCAGUCUCCACCCAACUCCUGGCACUGCUCCCAGGGGAUCGGGUCUCCACUCCAGCUUUCUCAAUUAAAGACGAUUUAUACAACUGAA